CUCUUCCGGGCAAAAUGGCGAUGGGACUAAUGUGCGGACGCCGGGAGCUUCUGCGCUUGCUACAGUCCGGGCGUCGGGUCCACAGCGUCGCAGGGCCCUCGCAAUGGCUUGGGAAACCGCUGACCACACGGCUCCUAUUCCCAGCAGCCCCGUGCUGCUGUCGCCCACACUACCUCUUCCUUGCGGCUUCCGGCCCCCGCAGCCUCAGUACCUCUGCUAUCUCUUUUGCAGAAGUCCAGGUUCAGGCCCCUCCUGUUGUUGCUGCAACUCCCUCACCCACAGCAGUACCUGAGGUGGCUUCUGGAGAGACUGCAGAUGUAGUCCAAACUGCUGCAGAGCAGAGCUUCGCUGAACUGGGGCUGGGGUCAUACACCCCAGUGGGACUGAUCCAGAAUUUACUGGAAUUUAUGCAUGUUGAUCUGGGCCUACCUUGGUGGGGGGCCAUUGCUGCAUGUACAGUCUUUGCCCGCUGCCUGAUUUUUCCUCUCAUCGUGACGGGCCAGCGAGAGGCAGCCAGGAUCCACAAUCACUUGCCAGAGAUCCAGAAGUUUUCCAGUCGAAUCAGAGAGGCCAAGUUAGCAGGAGACCAUAUUGAGUAUUACAAGGCUUCCUCGGAGAUGGCACUUUACCAGAAAAAACAUGGUAUUAAACUCUAUAAACCUCUCAUUCUCCCUGUGACUCAGGCCCCAAUCUUCAUCUCCUUCUUCAUUGCUUUGAGAGAGAUGGCCAACCUUCCUGUGCCCAGCCUGCAGACAGGUGGCCUCUGGUGGUUCCAGGAUCUCACGGUAUCCGAUCCCAUCUACAUAUUACCACUGGCAGUCACUGCUACAAUGUGGGCUGUUCUUGAGCUAGGUGCUGAGACAGGUGUGCAAAGUUCUGACCUUCAGUGGAUGAGAAAUGUCAUCAGAAUGAUGCCCCUGAUAACCUUGCCCAUAACCAUGCAUUUCCCCACGGCAGUGUUUAUGUACUGGCUCUCCUCCAAUUUGUUUUCCCUGGUCCAAGUAUCCUGUCUCCGGAUUCCAGCAGUACGCACUGUACUUAAAAUCCCCCAGCGUGUUGUACAUGACCUGGACAAAUUACCUCCACGGGAAGGCUUCCUAGAGAGCUUCAAAAAAGGCUGGAAAAAUGCUGAAAUGACGCGUCAGCUGCGAGAGCGUGAACAACGCAUGCGGAAUCAGUUGGAGCUAGCAGCCAGGGGUCCUUUACGACAGACCUUUACCCACAACCCUCUCCUACAACCUGGAAAGGAUAACCCUCCCAAUAUCCCUAGCAGCAGCAGCAAACCAAAGUCAAAGUAUCCCUGGCACGACACACUUGGCUGACUUAUGUUCUGUGCGCAUUCUGGCAGGAAUUCUGUCUCUUCAGAGACUCAUCCUCAAAACAAGACUUGACACUGUGUCCUUGCCCCAGUCCUAGGAACUGUGGCACACAGAGAUGUUCAUUUUAAAAACGGAUUUCAUGAAACACUCUUGUACUUAUGUUUAUAAGAGAGCACUGGGUAGCCAAGUGAUCUUCCCAUUCACAGAGUUAGUAAACCUCUGUACUACAUGCUGCUUCCUGAUACUUAUUGAACAGGGAAAUCAGUGUGCACUUCAGAAAACUGAAGAAUACCCAGCAUUUUGGGAGGCCGAGGUGGGUGGAUCACCUGAGAUCAGGAGUUUGAGACCAGCCUGGCCAACAUGGGGAAACGCCAUCUCUGCUGUUUUACAAAAAUAGCCACACGUGGUGGUGCACACCUGUAGUCCCAGCUACUCGGGAGGCUGAGGCAGGAGAAUUGCUUGAAUCCGAGAGGCGGAGGUUGCAGUGAGCCAAGAUCGCACCACCGCACUCCAGCCUGGGCAAUAGAGGGAGACUGUCUCAAAAAAAAAAGAAAACUGAAGAAUAGAGUGAGUCAUGAUUGCUUUUGCUGGCCCAUGGCCUUGGAAAAUAUAAUGUUUUAACCUGGCAUUAAGGGUUUAAACUUCCACCCAGGCGCAGUGGCUCACGCCAGUAAUCCCAGCACUUUUGGGAGGCCAAGGCGGGCGGAUCACGAAGUCAGCAGAUCGAGACCAUCCUGGCCAACAUGGUGAAACCCCGUCUCUACUAAAAAAAAAAAAAAAAAAAUUAGCCGGGCAUGGCGGCGGGUGCCUGUAUUCCCAGCUACUUGGGAGGCUGAGGCAGGAGAAUGGCGUGAACCCAGGAGGCAGAGCUUGCAGUGAGCCGAGAUUGCGCCACUGCACUCCAGCCUGGGCAAGAGAGUGAGACUCCUUCUCAAAAAAAAAAAAAAAAAAAAAAAAAAAAAAACAGUUUAAACUUCCAACCCAUGCAUGUGUUGUUCUAUGCACAUUUGGAUUGCAGUCUAGAGGUGUGGCUGAUAAGUUGAAUGUUGAGAUUGUAUCUAAAUAUAGUAACCGCACUUCUUGAUCCCAAGAUUACUUUAAAAAUUUCAAGAAGUAGAUGUGUGCAAAUUCUUAGUGAUAAUUAAGAAUGAAAGUUCCAGGCUGGGCAAAGUGGCUCACACCUAUAAUCUCAGCACUUUGGGAGGCUGAGGUGGGUAGAUCACUUGAGUCCAGGAAUUUGAGACCAGCCUGGGCAACAUGGCGAGACCUUGUCUCUGCUAAAAAGUUAGCUGAGCAUGGUGGUGCUUGUCCAUAGUCCCAGCUACCUGGGAGGCUGAGGUGGGAGGAUAGCUUAAGCCCAGGAGGUUGAGGCUGCAGUGAUCCAAGAUCAUGCUGCUAUACUCCAGCCUUGGCUACAGAGCAAGAUCCUGUCUCAAAAAGGAAGUUCAUGUCAUUUUUAUGUAACAAUCCAACAUUUGACUAGAGCA